AUCCCUCUCAGCUCUUGCUAAGUGAUCACUAGCUUGCCUCCAAGCUCUCUCACUAUGAACAGACAAGUUUGCAAGAAAUCCUUCAGUGGCAGGAGCCAGGGUUUCUCUGGCCGCUCUGCUGUGGUCUCCGGCAGCAGCAGGAUGAGCUGUGUGGCCCGCUCUGGGGGAGCUGGUGGAGGGGCCUGUGGCUUCAGGAGCGGAGCAGGCAGCUUUGGCAGUCGCAGCCUCUACAACCUGGGCAGCAACAAGAGCAUCUCCAUCAGCGUGGCAGCUGGCAGCUCCCGGGCUGGAGGCUUUGGGGGAGGGCGGAGCAGCUGUGGCUUUGCAGGUGGCUAUGGAGGUGGCUUUGGGGGCAGCUAUGGUGGUGGCUUUGGUGGUGGCAGAGGAGUAGGUAGUGGUUUUGGAGGGGCUGGUGGCUUUGGUGGAGCUGGUGGCUUUGGUGGUCCUGGUGUAUUUGGUGGGCCUGGCAGCUUUGGUGGUCCUGGUGGCUUUGGCCCUGGGGGCUUUCCUGGGGGAAUUCAGGAAGUGAUUGUAAACCAGAGUCUCCUGCAGCCCCUCAAUGUGGAGAUCGACCCCCAGAUUGGGCAAGUAAAGGCCCAGGAGCGGGAACAGAUCAAGACCCUCAACAACAAGUUUGCCUCCUUCAUCGACAAGGUGCGGUUCCUGGAACAGCAGAACAAGGUCCUGGAGACCAAGUGGGAACUGCUCCAGCAGCAGACCACAGGCUCAGGGCCCAGCAGCCUGGAGCCUUGUUUUGAAUCCUACAUCAGCUUCCUAUGCAAGCAGCUAGAUUCACUUCUAGGGGAGAGGGGGAACCUGGAGGGAGAGCUGAAAAGCAUGCAGGACCUGGUGGAAGACUUCAAAAAGAAGUAUGAAGAUGAAAUCAACAAACGCACUGCCGCAGAGAAUGAGUUUGUGGGGCUCAAGAAGGAUGUGGAUGCGGCUUUCAUGAACAAGGUGGAGCUGCAGGCCAAAGUGGACAGCCUGACAGAUGAAGUCAGCUUCCUGAGGACCCUCUAUGAGAUGGAGCUGUCCCAGAUGCAAAGCCAUGCCAGUGACACGUCUGUGGUUCUGUCCAUGGACAACAACCGCUGCCUGGACCUGGGCAGCAUCAUUGCCGAGGUCCGCGCCCAGUAUGAGGAGAUUGCCCAGAGGAGCAAGUCUGAAGCUGAGGCCCUGUACCAGACCAAGCUUGGGGAGCUGCAGACCACAGCUGGCAGGCAUGGGGAUGACCUGAGGAACACCAAGAGUGAGAUCAUGGAGCUCAACAGGAUGAUCCAGAGGCUACGGGCUGAGAUUGAAAAUGUCAAGAAGCAGAAUGCCAACCUGCAGACGGCAAUUGCAGAGGCUGAGCAGCGUGGAGAGAUGGCCCUCAAGGACGCCAAUGCCAAGCUCCAAGACUUGCAGACUGCCCUACAGAAGGCUAAGGAUGACCUGGCUCGGCUCCUGCGUGACUACCAGGAGCUGAUGAACGUCAAGCUGGCCCUGGAUGUGGAGAUUGCCACCUACCGCAAGCUGCUGGAGGGAGAGGAGUGCAGGAUGUCUGGAGAAUGUCAGAGUGCCGUGUGCAUUUCAGUGGUCAGCAAUGUCACCAGCACAAGUGGCAGCUCUGGCAGUAGCCGUGGAGUUUUUGGAGGGGUCAGUGGCAGUGGCAGUGGUGGCUACAAAGGCGGCAGCAGCAGCAGCAGCAGCAGUGGCUAUGGAGUCAGUGGCGGCAGCGGCAGUGGCUAUGGAGGGGUCAGCAGUGGCAGCACUGGGGGCAGGGGUAGCAGCGGGAGCUACCAGAGCAGCAGUAGUGGGAGCAGGCUCGGCGGUGCAGGUAGCAUCUCCGUGAGCCACAGUGGAAUGGGCUCCAGCUCUGGCAGCAUCCAGACUUCUGGAGGAAGUGGCUACAAGUCUGGUGGUGGAGGCAGCACCAGUAUCCGCUUCUCCCAGACCACGAGCUCAAGCCAGCAUAGCUCCACCAAGUGAUCUACUGUUCCAAAUCUCUAUAACCACCUGCUUCCCACUCAGCCUGCAAUAGUGUUUCCCACUCUCUGCUUGGCAUCAAUAGAUGCAUAAGGGUCAACCACAUUUUUCCUCAAGUUCCCUGGAGAAGAAGCUGAACUCCUGGUUUCUCCAUCCCCAUGACCUUCCCAGGGCCAUGGAGGUCCUGCUGCUGGUCUGGGAUGAUGAUGCCCCUGGAAACCUUCCUGCAAUGGCCCCUUACUUUGGACAGCAACCCCUGAGCCCAAGCCAGUUUUGGCCUUCACAGCCUGGCCUGUUCCCACUCUGGCCCAUCUCCCUUUCUUACUGGGAGUUGGAGAUUUGAAGCCAGUCAUCUCAGCACUGUCUGAGGAGGGCAGAGCCAUGGGUUCUGUGCUGGAGGGUGCACGGCCAAGAUCUCCAGACUGCUGGUUCCCAGGGAACCCUCCCUACAUCUGGGCUUCAGAUCCUGACUCCCUUCUGUCCCCUAAUUCCCUGAGCUGUAGAUCCUCUGGUGAUGAGUAUGUUGCACUUUCUUUUCUCAAUAAAUUGCACUGAACUUCA